AUGGUUUCCUUAGAUUAUUUUCAAUCAGGCAAACAUGGCGACUCCGGCCCUGUGAUUCCAGAGGUCCCCUUUGAACCAUCGAAGCCCCCAGUCAUUGAGGGGCUUAGCCCCACUGUUUACAGGAAUCCAGAGAGUUUCAAGGAAAAGUUCCUUCACAAGACCCACGAGAACCCGGUGGUACCCAUAGGUUGCCUGGCCACGGCGGCCGCCCUCACCUACAGCCUCUAUUCCUUCCACCGGGGCAACAGCCAGCGCUCUCAGCUCAUGAUGUGCACCUGGAUCGCCGCCCAGGGUUUCACGGUCACAGCCAUCUUGCUGGGUCUAGCUGUCACCGCUAUGAAGUCUCAACCCUGA